CUUCAGACUGAGUCUCGCCCUGUUGCCCGGGCUGGAGUGCAGUGGCACGAUCUCUGCUCACUGCAAGCUCUGCCUCCCAGGUUCAUGCCAUUCUGCUGCCUCAGCCUCCCGAGUAGCUGGGACUACAGGCAUCCACCACCACGCCCUGCUAAUUUUUUGUAUUUUUAGUAGAAACAGUGUUUCACUGUGUUAGCCAGGGUGGUCUCAAUCUCCUGACCUCCUGAUCCGCCUGCCUCGGCCUCCGAAAGUGCUAGGAUUACAGGCGUGAGCCACUGCACGUGGCCUGUCUGCUCUUAAAGAGAUUAAUAAAUUAGAGGGAAAACUCAGAAUGUCUUUGUAAUUUAAAUUUUUGUUAAGGGAAAAUAAUAACAUUUAAAAUAAUUGUUUCUCUGUGUUAAUAAUGGGUACUGUACAAUUAAUUUCCUUUUUUAAAAAAUAUAUUUUUUGAGACAGAGUUUCUCUCUUGUUGCGCAGGGUGGAGUGCAAUGGCACAAUCGCGGCUUAUUGCUACCUCUGCCUCCGGGGUUCAAGCGAUUCUCCUGCCUCAGCCUCCCAGGUAGCUGGGACUACAGGCACACACCACCACACCCAUCUGGUUUUUUUGUAUUUAGUAGAGAUGGGAUUUCACCAUGUUGGUCAGGCUGGUCUCGAACUCCUGACCUUAGGUGAUCCACCCGCCUCAGCCUCCCAAAGUACUGGGAUUACAGGCAUGAGCCACCAUGCCCAGUCCUUUUUUAAUUUUUUUUUUUUUUUUAAUUGUUGUCACCAGGCUGGAGUACGGUGGCACAAUCAUGGCUUACUACAACCUGGAACUCCUGGGCUCAAGUGAUCCUCCAACCUCAGCCUCCCAAGUAGCUGAGACUAUAGGCACGCACCACCACACCUGGCUAAUUUUUGUGGUAUUUUUGUAGAGGUGGGGUUUUGCUGUGUUGACUAGGCUAGUCUCAAACUCCUGGGUGAAUCCUCCUGCCUUGGCUUCCCAAAGUGCUGGGAUUACAGGUAUUAGCCACUGCACCCAGCCCAAACUGUAUUUUUUUGUCUUCUAGUACACCUUGUAAUUUUUUAUUGAAAGCUGGGCAUGGGCCGGGCAUGGUGGCUCAUGCCUGUAAUCCUAGCACUUUGGGAGGCUGAGGCAGGUGGAUUGCCUGAGUUCAGGAGUUCAAAAUCAGCCUGGGCAACAUGGUAAAACCCCGUCUCUGCAAAAAAAAAAAAAAAAAAAAAAAAAAAUACAAAAAUUAGCUAGGCAUGGUAAGUGCAUGCCUGUAGGCCCAGCUACUUGGGGGGGCUGAGGCAGGAGGAUCACUUUAGCCCCGGAGGCAAAAGUUGCAAUGAGCUGAGAUGGCGCCACUGCCCUUCAGCCUGGGGGACAGAGUGAGACCCUGUUUCAAAAAAAAAAAAAAAUGCUGGGCAUGUUUUACUAGGUAAAAGUAACUGAGAUACAUAAGCCUUUAGUGUGAGGCAUUACGUUUAUCUGACUUAGGAUUGGGCUGUGUUUUGUAUUAACAUUUUUUGUAGCUGUAGGUGUGAGAACUAAUAUUUCCUCCAGUGUUCUUAUUUUUGUUUACUUUGUUGUCUUGGGGUUCCUUAGAGACUUCUUAAAUAAGAUCUGAGACAUGCAGUUAUAUAUUUUUCUUUUUUAGUUUUUUAAUUCCUUGCAAGUAUUGCACAAAUGCAGUUCUUUGAGUAACGUCCUGUUGUUAUACAAAAGCCUUCGUGGCCAGGCAUGGUGGCUGACAAUUGUAAUCCCAGCACUUUGGGAGUCCAAGGCAGACAGAUUGCUUUAGCCCAAGAAUUUGAGAUUUGUAGACAAAUGGAGACAUGGCGAACCGUCUCUACAGAAAAUACAAAUAUUAACCAGGCAUGGUGUCAUGCACCUGUACUCACAGCUACUCAGGAGGCUGAGGUAGGAUCAUCUGAACCCGGGAGGCAGUUUGCAGUGAGCCAUGAUCAUGCCACUGCACUCCAGCCUGGGUGACAGAGCAAGACCCUGUCUCAAAAAAAAAAAAAAAAAAAAAAAAAAAAACACCUCUUGAUAGUAAGGUUUCAGUAUUCUGUUGUAGUCUUUUAGUGAAUCUGUGUACCUGGGCUGUGAUAUUCACAGUUGCUUCUCAGUUCACACUUCCUCCUUAGUUGAGAUUGGAAGGCUGGGAUUGGGUUUUUCACUUCCCUUGGGUCAGUUAGCUCUGAUAAAACUCCAGUUGGUUAACCUCUGGUGAAAUCUUUUCUCUUGAAGGCAGGCCUUUUUAAAAAGAACAGAUUACUUUGGAAUUACUUCAGAAUGGCUACUUUCCCCCUUCCCCCUGCCAGAAGCAUGCAGGGAAUUUUCUUCCAUCCUCACUGUGAGAACCUCCUGCGUUCAAGUGACCCUCCUGCUUCAGCCUCCUGAGUAUCUGGGACUACAGGUGCACACCACCAUACCUGGCUAAUUUUUGUAUUUUUAGUAGAGAGCAGGUUUUGCCAUGUUGCCCAGGUUGGUCUUGAACUCCUGGGCUCAAGCAGUCUGUCCACCUUGGCCUUCCAAAGUGUUGGGAUUACAGGCAUGUACCACCACACUUGGCCUUUUUUUUUAAAAUAGUAUUGUAAAUAUUUGGGUUUUUAAAAUAAAACAUUUAUUCUCAGAGUUGUGGAGGCUAGAAGUUGGAAAUCAAGGUGUCAGCAGGGUCAGAUUGCCUCUGAAACCUCUGGGGAAUCCUUCCUUGCCUCUUCCUAGUUUCUGUUGGUUUGCCAGCGUUUUUGGUGUUCCUUGGCUUGUAGAUGCAUCACCCCAAUAAUCUGUCUUUAUGUGGCAUCCUCCCUAUAUGUCUGUCUUAACAUGUUGACCAGGCUGGUCUCGAACUCCUGACCUCAGGUGUUCUACCUGCCUUGGCCUCCCAAAGUGCUGGGAUUACAGGCGUGAGCCAUCGUGCCUGGCCUGUUUUUACUUUUUAACUUUCUGCUAAAAUUUUUAAACUUGUACUGAAGUUGAGAAAAUAGCAUAAUAGAUAUCAUCACCCAGUUGCUUUUUCUUUUUCUUUUUUGUAGAGACGGAGAUCUCACUUUGCUGCCCAGGCUGGUCUUGAACUCCUGGGCUUAAACAAUCCUCCUGCCUCAGUCUCCCAAAGUGCUGGGAUUACAGGUGUGAGCCACCACUCCUCCUGGCCUCCACUUUCGGUAGUUAUGAACAUGUGGCUAGUUUGUCUGUCAGAUUCCCACUCCCUUCUAGAUUAUUUUGCUGUUUGUUUGUUUGUUGUUUGAGAUGGAGUCUCACUGUCUCCCAGGCUGGAGUGCAAUGGUGCGAUCUCGGCUUACUGCAACCUCUGCCUCCUGGGCUCAGACGAUUCUCCUCCCUCAGCCUCCUGAGUAGCUGGGACUACAGGCGUGCACCACCACACCUGGCUAAUUUUUUGUGUUUUUAGUAGAGACAGGGUUUCACCAUGUUGGUUAGGCUGGUCUCAAACUCUUGACCUCAGGUGAUCUACCCACCUCAGCCUCCCAAAGUGUUAGGAUUACCAGCGUGAGCCAAUGUACCUGUCCCCUUCUAGAUUAUUUUGAAACAAAUCUUCUGAGUUAUUUUGCAGCAAACCCCAGAAUUCUGUCAUUGUACAGUGAAUAAUUCAUUGUGGAUCUUUAACAUACAAGGACAUUUUUAUGAAACCAAAUCAAUUGUCUUAUUAUGUCCAACAAAAGAAACACUAAUUUUUGAAUAUGUAAUGACACAGUACAUGCUCAGGUUUCCUUGACUUCUGACUUACCUUUUUACAGUUACAUUAUUCUUCUUAAUGGUUGUAAUCAUUUAGUUUACUUUCUAGUCCUUUUAUGUCACAAGCAGUCUUAGAGUACAAAUGUUAUAUCACAUACAGAGGAUUGUAUUGUGUAGGAAAAACAUGGACAACAAAGACUGAAUUGAAAAGGUGAUACUGGAGAGUAGGACUUGAUGUGAAGAAGUUUGAGGAGUAGCUUUGACUGUUUUUCUUUUCUCUUUAAUAAUCUUAAAGGUUUCUUAUGGGGGGAGCGCUGAGACAGGAUACACCACAGUCACCCAGGCAGGAGUGCCAGUGGUAAGAUCACGGCUCUCUGCAGCCUGGGAUUCCUGGGCUCAGGUGAUUUUCCCACUUCAGCCUCCCGCAUUGCUGGGACUAUGGCCAUGCACCACCACACCCACACCUACCUAAUUUUUUUGUAGAGACAGGGUUUCACCAUGUUGUCUGGACUGAUCUUUUUUUUUUUUUUCCAUAAGGAUAGAGAUGGGCUGGUCUUGAACUCCUGGGUUCAAAUGAUCAGCCCAUCUCCACCACCCAAAGAGCUGGGAUUACAGGUGUGAGCCACUGUGCCUGGCCUAAUCUUAGGAUUGAAGUAUAUAAAUUCUAAAAGUUGAGUAAGUGUAUAAUAAAAACUGAGUGAUAAAGUAUUGUGUCAUGGUGUAAAUGGCAGUGUUUUUUUCUUACUGGCAUACAUUGAGAUGUCCUCUAACUGAAAUCUUAGAAGUGAGCCGGGUGCAGUGGCUCACGCCUGUAAUCCCAGCACUUUGGGAGGCUGAGGCAGGCAGAUCAUAAGGUCAGGAGUUCGAGACCAGCCUGGCCAAUGUGGUGAAACCCUGUGUCUACUAAAAAAUAUGUAAGAAAUUAGCCAGGCGUGGUGCUGUGCGCCUGUAGUCCCAGCUACUCAGGAGGUUGAGACAGAAGAAUCGCUUCAACCCGGGUGGUGGAGGUUGCAGUGAGCCGAGAUUGCCCCACUGCAUUUCAGCCUGGGCGACAGAGCAAGACACCAUCUCAAAAAAAAAAAUAAGUAAAAGAAAAGCUCUGUCUUGACUCUUGAAUCAGUUUUAAAACCUGGCUUCACUGAUUAUUAGCUUUGUGACUUUGUUGCCUCAGCUUCCUUAUUGGUAAGCACGUAAGUUUGUUUUAAGAUUGAGUUAUUACAUGUACAUCAGUUAAAAUAUUGCCUGUAAAUUAUAUAUAGAUAUUGAGCUGGGAGUGGUGGUUUACGCCUCUAAUCCCAACAGUUUGGGAGACUGAGGCGGGAGAAUUGCCUUAGCUCAGAGGUUUGAGGCAGCGGUGAGCUAUGAUUGUACCACUGUACCUCCUGUCUGGAUGAUAAAGCGAUGUAUUAGGUAUUAUUGUUGAUCGUUCAGCAACAUUACCCACUGUUUCCUUGAAAUAUUAUUCCUGUAGUGUCAGUGAUAUCAGACUAUCCAAAUAUCUUUUUCUUCCUUUCUUCUUUCCUUUCUUUCCUUUUCCCUUUCCCUCCCCUUCCUCCUGCCUUUCCUUUUUUCCUUUUUUCUUUUUUUUCUUUUGAGACAGAGUCUCGCUCUGUCCCCCAGGUGGGGAGUGCAGUUGUGCGAUCUCGGCUCACUGCAAGCUCCGCCUCCUGGGUUCACGCCAUUCUCCUGCCUCAGCCUCCGGAGUAGCUGGGACUAUAGGCGCCCGCCACCACGCCCGGCUAGUAGGUUUUUUUUGUUUUUUUUGUUUUUUUUUUUUUGUAUUUUUAGUAGAGACGGGGUUUCACUGUGUUAGCCAGGAUGGUCUCCAUCUUUUGACCUCGUGAUCCACCCGCCUCGGCCUCCCAAAGUGCUGGGAUUACAGGCGUGAGCCACCGCGCACAGCCCCCCACCUUUUUUUUUUUUUUUUAAGGAGUCUUACUUUGUCGCCCAAGCUGGAGUACUGUGCUUCUGUCUCGGCUUACUGCUCCCUCCGUGUCUUGGAUUCAAGCAGUUCUCCUGCCUCAGCCUCCAGAGUAGCUGGGAUUACAGGCACGCACCACCAUGCCCCCAGCUAAUUUUUGUAUUUUUAGUAGAGGCGGGGUUUCACCAUGUUGGCCAGGCUAGUCUCGAACUCUUGACCUUAGAUGAUCCGCCCACCUUGACCUCUCAAAGUGUUGGUAUUACAGGCGUGAGCCAUGGCGCCCGGUCUUUCCUAUCUUUCUGACUGUAUCUUCAGAUCACUCCUGAACCCGAGACCUGAAUUUUUCAUUUACCUACUUGGUUCUUUGGAUUUUCACAGAUACCUUGUAUCCAACAUGUCUCAAACUGAUUUUUCCCCUCUCCCUCAAACCCUGACUUCUCAAUUCUUUGUUUCCUUAUCUUUAUUAUACUGUCAUCCACCCAGCAAAAAAUCCCCUCUUCUAAGAUCAUAGCUUUUAGUUAGUAACUAAGUCCUUUAGAUUUUACUUCCUGUCUGCCUUAAUUCAUCUUCUUUUCAUUGCACUGGACUUUAUUGGCAUCUCUCACUGGUUUCCUAAGUAUUCUCUCUAAUCCCCCUCCAGCCAUUUCCCCCUACUCCAGCCAGGUGAUCUCUAAGAGACCCAGAUCUGAUUGUUACAACACUUCAAAUUUUUAUUAUUCUUCAUGACCCUGAAUAAUCUGGCUUUUGACUGCUUCUCCUGCCUCAUUUCAUCAUUUUCAUUCUUUGUAUUGUAGUCACAUUGGCGGCAUUUCAAUUCCUAAACCUGUCAAGUCCUCGUUUGCCUCCAUUUUGCACAGCGUGUACGCUCUGCCUUAAGUGCUGGCUUUUCCUAAAGUUAAGUCUUUUAAAACUAAUUUCCUCAAGGAAGCUUCCUCUUACUUUCUAGAUUUUCUGUCUGCUAAAUGUUCUUCAUAGUAUCCUGUACUUCAUUUAAAAAUUAUAUAAUUAGUUCUUCAGUACCUUAGAAUGAAAUAACUAUUGAUACAGGUUAGAGAAAAUUUCUAGUUGAUCAUUAUACUACCAAUAUCUGUUAUAAUGCCUUGCAAAUAGCAAGUACUUAGUAAAUAUUCAUGGAAUUGAUAAAUUCAGACUUGAAUUACUCUUCAUUGUAGAUUGAGUAAAGUUUGACAGAAGUCCAGAACUUAACUUUUUUUUUUAAGAGAUGGAGUCUCACUCUGUCACACAGGCUGGUGUGUAGUGGCACAGUCAUAGCUUACUGCACCCUUGACCUCUUGGGCUCAAGUGAUUCUCCCACUUCAACUUCCUGAAUAGCUGGGAUUACAGACACACGUUUUUUGUUUUUUUUGUUUUUUUUCCACGCUGUAGAGAUGGGAGUUUCACUAUAUGGCCCAGGCGGGUCUUAAGCUCCUGGGCUCAAGUGAUCCUCCCUCCUUUGCCCCACAAAGUGUUGGGAUUACAGGUGUGAUUUAAAAAAUGCUAGCUGCAGCCUGGUGUGGUGGCUUAGCCUGUAAUCCCAGCACUUUGGGAGGCUGAGGCUGGUAGAUCUUGAGGUCAGGAGUUCAAGACCAGCCUGGCCAACAUGGUGAAACCCCAUCUCUACCAAAAAUUCAGCAAUUAGCCGGGCAUGGUGGUGGGCGCCUAUAAUUGCAGCUACUCAGGAGGCUAAGGCAGAAGGAUCGCUUGAACCCCCAAGAGGUGGAGUUUGCAGUGAGCUGAGAUUGCGCCACUGCACUCCAGCCUGGGCAACAGAGUGAGACUCCGUCUCAAAAAAUAAUAAUAAUAAUAAUUGCUAGCUGCUAUAGCUUCUUUUUUUUUUUUUUUUUUUGAGACAGAGUCUCACUCUGUUGUCCGGUGGAGUGCAGUGGCGUGAUCUCUGCUCACUGCAACCUCCGCCUCUCGGGUUCAAGCAGUUCUCCUGCCUUAGAAUUUCAAGUAGCUGGGAUUUACAGGAGUGUGCCACUAUGUCCAGUCUCUUGUACUAUUUUUAUCUUUUAUUUUCAAGACAGAGUCUUGCUUUGUCGCCCAGGCUAGAGUGCAGUGGCACGAUCUCAACUCACUGCAACCUCUGCCUCCCGGGUUCAAGCGAUUCUCCUGCCUCAGCUGGUCUCGAACUCCUGACGUCAGGUGAUCCGCCUGCCUCAGCCUCCCAAAGUGCUGGGAUUACAGGCAUGAGCCACGGCGCCCGGCCAUCUUGUACUCUUUUCAAUGUGGAUAUCAGAAAAUUUUAAAUUUACAUAGUGGCUUACAUUAUAUUGUAUUGGAUACUGCUCGUCUAGAACUUGUUUUUAGUAAGGAUCAUACAUGUGUCUCCAUGGCCUCAGUUUUUCAUUAUUCUCCCAAUCCCUUUGUUUUCAUGUCACUUCUGCUUUGGGACUGUUAUGUGCCAUAAGCUUCAGAAAACACGGUGGCUCACACCUGUAAUCCCAGCACUUUGGGAAGCCGAGGCAGGUGGAUCACCAGAGGUCAGGAGUUUGAGACCACCCUGGCCAACAUGAUGAAACCUUGUCUCUAGUACAAAUACAAAAAAAUUAGCCAGGCGUGGUGGCGGGCGCCUGUAAUCCCAGCUACUUGGGAGGCUGAGGCAGGAGAAUUCCUUGAACCCAGGAGUCAGAGGUUGCAGUGAGCUGGGCAACACAGCAAGACUCCAUCUCAAAAAAAUAAAAAAAAAAUUUAACUGCCUAGAAGGUAGAAAUCGAGUGUAUUUCUUAGGCCUUUGAAUAAUAGGGGAAAGAUAAGUCAUUUAUAUUAAAUUAUGAGAAAAUAAUGGCAACUGUUAAGCUUUUAAAGUAUUAUUUCCAACUAAAUUAGGAAGAACUAAAUUUCACUUUUACAUAUGCAUGACAAUGAUGAGCAGGGCUCCUAAAACAGUUGUGGCUUGACUAGGAAACAAAUAAUAAUUUUUUUAUAUCAAUAAGAAUUACUUGUAACUUUAGGGGGCAUUUAGAAUUAUAUUUGUCUUAUUUGAGAUUUGGAUUUAAAUUUUAUUUUAGAGCAUUUUUUAAAAAAUAAAUAGAAGUGAGGCUAAUAUUGUUAAUUAUUCUCUUUAAAAAAUACAGUAUUUGCUUUGGGUUAAAAUUUUCUGCCCCAACAUCAUUAUCAAGAGUCAGCAUAUUACAAUGAUAAAUUUAGCAUUUACUGUGUGGCAGGCAUUGUUCUAUAUACUUUAUUCGUUAAAUUCACCAGCGAACCCUAUGAGGAACUAUCUUAUCCUUAGUUGACAGAGGAUGAAACUGGAGUACAAAGUAGUUAAUUAACUUGUUCAUAGCUAGUAAGUUUUAAAAAGGUUAAACAACAAUAUACUUUGUAUUUAGUCCUUAAAUGAUAAAAUCUUCCAGUGUUUAGUUUUUCCCACUAGAAUGUAAGCUCCAAGUGGGCAGGGACUUAGGUUUUGUUCACUAACAUUUGAGAUAGCAUAUACUAGAACCUAGUCAUUAUUUGAAAGAAUUUUUACAGUGAUGAUGGUAACAAUGACAAUAUCAUUUCACUGAGAGAUGGCCUUGGAAAUACAUUAGAACCGCUUUGAGUUCUUCACUGUUGGUUGUUGACAAUAAUGUUUUUUUUAUCUCAUUCAAAUUAGCUUCAACGUUAUGUGCUAUUUUGCAUGCUUCAUGUAUAUCUUAAUAAAAUAGUUGAUUUGAAAAUUGCUAACUUCUAUAGCUUCUUCCCUCUUUUUUUUUUUUUUUUUUUUGGUGACAGAGUCUUGCUUCGUAGCCCAGGCUGGAGUGCAGUGGUGUGAUCUUGGUUCACUGCAACCUCUGCCUCCCGGGUUCAAGCAAUUCUCAUGCCUCAGCCUCCUGAGUAGCUGGGAUUACAGACAUGUGCUACCAUGCCCAGUUAAUUUUUGUAUUUGUAGUAGAGACAGGGUUUUGCCAUAUGGGCCAGGCUGGUCUCAAGUUUCUUGCCUCAAAUGAUUCAUCUGCCUCGGCCUCCUAGAGUACUGGAAUUACAGGGGUGAAACAUCCUGCCUGGCCUAGCUGCUAUAGCUUUUAUAUAUCUCUGUUCCUUUUGUGCAUUAGAAAUGCCUUGAAGCCCCCAGGGAACAUCAGGAAAAAAAAAAAAAAAAAAAAAAACAACCAGAGGUCCCGCUAUGUGUUUAGCUGAGUUGGGAGAAGAAAGUUUAGAAAAGCAAUCUUUGACCUAUCCUUAUGAAAAAUUUACAGUGAUAACACAAUUCUUCAGAAUUUCACCCAAAAGCUACAGCUGCCUUGGUUGUUGCAGUCAUUGAAGUGAAUAACACAUUAUUUUAUUAUUUAUUUUUAGAUACUACAUUUUUUUCUUAGACUGUGGAAACAGGACUGUGAAAUUAAUUUUGUAAAAUCGGGCUUUAAUUUUUUUUUUUUUUUUUUUGAGACAGAAUCUCGGUCUAUCAUCCAGGCUGCAUGUAGUGGUGCAAUCUCGGCUCACUGCAACCUCCACCUCCCAAGUUCAAGCCAUUCUUCUGCCUCAGUCUCCCGAGUAGCUGGGACUACAGACGAGCAAAAAUCAAAUUAAAGUAGAUCUUGUAGAUGAGAAUUUUACAGAAUUAAGAGGAGAAAUAGCAGGACCUCCAGACACACCAUAUGAAGGAGGAAGAUACCAACUAGAGAUAAAAAUACCAGAAACAUACCCAUUUAAUCCCCCUAAGGUCCGGUUUAUCACUAAAAUAUGGCAUCCUAAUAUUAGUUCCGUCACAGGGGCUAUUUGUUUGGAUAUCCUGAAAGAUCAAUGGGCAGCUGCAAUGACUCUCCGCACGGUAUUAUUGUCAUUGCAAGCACUAUUGGCAGCUGCAGAGCCAGAUGAUCCACAGGAUGCUGUAGUAGCAAAUCAGUACAAACAAAAUCCCGAAAUGUUCAAACAGACAGCUCGACUUUGGGCACAUGUGUAUGCUGGAGCACCAGUUUCUAGUCCAGAAUACACCAAAAAAAUAGAAAACCUAUGUGCUAUGGGCUUUGAUAGGAAUGCAGUAAUAGUGGCCUUGUCUUCAAAAUCAUGGGAUGUAGAGACUGCAACAGAAUUGCUUCUGAGUAACUGAGGCAUAGAGAGCUGCUGAUAUAGUCAAGCUUGCCUCUUCUUGAGGAGCACCAACAUCUGUUAUUUUUAGGAUUCUGCAUAGAUUUCUUUUAAACUGGCAUUCUUGCCUAAUGAUGUUAUCUAGGCACCAUUGGAGACUGAAAAAAAAAAAUCCCUGCUCUGUAAAUAAAGCUAAUUAAACGUCUGUGUAAAUUUAAAAAGGGGAAAUACUUUAAUUUUUUUUCUUAAUAGUGUAAAAAUUCCCUGAGCUAAGCUAAAACCAUGGAAGAAACAUGCUACUUUAGUGUUUAGCAGUGUACCAAGACUAGCAAGAGUUUGCUUCAGGAUUUUGUUGAAUAAUUAAGAUAAUAUUUUGAGUGUGUCAGGGCCAUUCAAAUUGUUGGUGUUGCAUCACAGCUACCUUAACUGUUUUUAACAUGGAUCCUCUGUGCCUGUGAAUUUACUUGCAUGCUUGUACUUGACUUCUUAGGAUGGGUAGCUGAAAAGACCACCAUUUUAAGCAUUUGAGAAUUCUUAAAUAUGAAAUUUAUUCAGAAUUGAAGAUGGUGACCUAUUCAGAGCCUUUUUGUCCUUGUCAACAGACUGGGACAGUGUCUGAUUCCCCCUUCACCCCCCCCACCCCCGCCUUGCCACACACAGCUAAUAUUCUAAUGGUAAAUUUCUCUGUAUCAGGUGGGGAAAUGUGCUGAAGGACAGUAUGUAUCCCUUGCUUCAUUUUUAGGUCGUAGGUUUGGAAUGUCUUGUCCCAGUUCUUCAAACACUCUUAAAUUUUUCUUAAGUAAUGUAAAAAUGGAACUGCCAAUUUUAUUUCUCUUGCAAAAAUAGUAAAUACUUGAUGUUACAUUAUUCCCAGGUUUAAUGAAAGAACCCAACUUAGUUUUUCAGUGAAUUUGACACCUAUUUUUUAGUGAUGAAAUUUUUCUUUGAGAACUGGCAAGGAUGCAGUCAGCUGUUUGCAGUUUUUAGCCUGAUUUUGGGGUCUAUAGAGAUUGCUUUAUUGGAUACUUCAAGUCAUUCUUGCUUGCACUUCCCCUAUUGACACAUGAAAGCUGUGUUGGUGUUUUAUUGUACAUACUUCAGAUGCACAUAGGAAUAGAAGUGUGUUAUAAAUCUAGCUUUCUUUAUGAUGUUUCUGAUAAUACGAGAAUUGAAAACUUUACCUUCUCUUGUACAUAGUCAGACUAUUUGUAUUAAAUUUACAUUUCAUUCUAAGUUCAAAAGUUUGAAAAUUAUUAGUUUUGCAAGAUCACACACUAAUGUAACCAUUUUAUGAAGGUUGAAGUGGAUUUAUGCAGGCAGUUCUAUAUAUAGAAAUACAAUUCUUUUUAAAUUUUUAGGACCAAUACAAAAUAACAAAAAUGUAAUGGAAUCAGACUGAAUUAAAGUAAGGCUGUAUAUUGAAAGUCAUAUUAUAAAAGGUUUGCUUUCUUUAAGUGUUAUUUAUCUUAAAUUAUAAUCGUUAAAUGUUUGGAAGAUAAUUUUUGAAUCAUAACGUCAGCAUAACUUCAUUUGACUUCUCAAUAAUCUUGAUACUAGAAGCAAUAAAAGAACCAUUAUUAAAUAUAUUGUAAUGUUAAAGAUGUGAAGGUUCUUCCAAAAAUUUGUAAGGCUUUCCUAAUUAACAGUAAACUCUUAUAGCUGAUAUUAUUACAUACUAAACACAAGUUGCUGUUUUUUCCCCAUAUGUUUGCUUACGCAUGUCUUUAUACAAUCACCUCUUUUUAUUGCUGUAGUUUAUUUUCUAAAGAUGCCAAAGGAAACAAGAUUUUUCUUUAUUUAUUUUAAAUACCUGAAACCUCGUACUUUAUAUUUUGAAGUAAGGUGGGAUUGUGUGAAAAUGUGGAUGGUUUUUCUCCAGUGUUGGUUAGAACUACUUUUUUUAAGUGGAGGGCAACUUGGUAGUAUUAGUAGAAUUUGGGUUUAAAAAUAUCAGACACAUCUACCCAGUUUAUUUUUUGCCUGUAUUAUCAGGGUAUAUUUAAUUGUCCUGUGGUUAAACAAAGGUGAGAGAGCUCAGAGGUUUCUAAAGGUCAAGCAUUUUACAUAUAUACAUACAUACAUGCUCUUGGAGGCAGCUAUAUCCUGCUUUGAUUUUUAUGCACAUGAGCCCUAUAGGGUUAUAUACUCAUCUAACUACACUUCAGCAUCCCCAGUGCCCAAGAAAUUGGAAAGUACAAUAUUUGGUUUGAGACAUUCUUCAUAAAAGAUUCUUUAUUAUAAAAAUUUACCUCAUUUACAUUUAAUGUGAUGAUCUUUUUUUUCCUUUCUGGUAUAUUUCCCACUGUACUGUUUGGUUUUUGUUAUUCUCUUGUCUGUGGGUAGAUUUAGUUACCCAAACAUAGAAACUAAAGCAAUUGCUUUUUUCCUCUGGUCUUAAAUAUGUUUGGACAAAAAGACACUAAAAGGUCAGGCCUAGGGGAAAAGUACCCUGGUGGAAAUUAUUUUUGUAAUUCUUAAUAUUUUUGAGUUGGCUCCGUUUGUCAGUUUUAAAAGCCUCAAAAAUUAUGUUAAAAAAAAAAUCCAGUGAAAUCCCAUUUAGGGCAGGCCGAUUUGUUAGAAGUCACUGAUGCUCCAGUAGGCUUUUGUUAUAAUCAGGCCUGUUUCCUGAGUAUGUGCCUCUUUUAAAAGAAGAAAUAAUUAGCUGUAUAGUAUUUCAGUACUGAUGAAUGAAUGAAUGAAUGAAUGGCAGUUAGUGGACCCAAAUAAGUAUUCAGUGGUAUAUAAAUAUUUGAGGAACUAGGUACUGAAUUAGGUGCUCUGAGUUGGCACCCCGAAAUGUUUGGAAUCACGACUAUGAUUUACUUAAACACGUAACACAUUCAAGGAUAUAUAAAUGGAGUCUAAGUAUUUUGCUUUUGAAGAGAAUAAUCUAUGAAAUGGAAGACUUGAUUUUUUUUUUCAUUUUUUAGAAGUAAUACACAUUUAUGAUUGUUGGCACAUAAAACUAUGCAAAAUAAUUCUUUUUAAGUAUCUGUAAGAAAGAAUUGGCAGUUUAAACGGAUUUUGCUUAUUUAUGCACUACAGAAUGCAGCAUACUGUAUUACUGUUGAGGCUGCUUAAUAAGUUUACCAAUGUGAAAAGCAGAUCUUGGGUAUAAGUGUAUGCCUGAUUUGAGCUUUUAAAACUGUGCAGUAGGUGUAUGGUAAUGUUUUACAAUCCUAUGUAGCAAAAUAGGAAAUUAUGAAUUUUUGUUGUUAUUGUUUUAAAGAUUUAAGAUGGAUUGGGGUAGGGAACAGCUGGAGCCAGGUAUACCUUCUAGUAUGUAGAGGGAAACAAUGUUUAGAUAGGAAAAAGGAAGCCGUCUGUUUACAGUUAACUUUAUUUCAUGGACUUCUACAAAAUGUUGUAUUAAUCACUUUUUCUAGUUCAAGGAAUUUCAAUUCCAGGGUACAAACCAUUGAUUUAAAAAUUACGUUUCCAUUCUUUUUAGUAUCAGUUUAAAGUAAAUGCUUACCAUCAGCCAGUUGCUGUCACUGGGAAGAAGGCAACUUGAAGUAUUUACUGAUAAAAUAGCCUUUAUUCCCAAGUGUGACUUUUCUUCAGUGUCUACAUAUUAUGUCACACGUUCUAUUUGCACUGCUGCAAUAUAGAUCAAAGAUCUUGUGGCAUAGGGGUAGGGGAGUGUUAGUAUCUCCCUUGUCCCAUUUGUUCUGUUACUGCUUCAUUGGACUGAUACACCCUCAUGAACUUGCAAUCACCUAAAUGGAAGUCUUGAAUGUGUCACCUUUUGCUUGGUUAUUUCAACCAUGCUGCUAUAUAUAAUCAGGUGUGGCACAGUUUGUCAGUUUGAUUAUAGGUGUGAGUGGAUAGAAAUCAUUACACUGUGCUGUUAACGAUCCUUGUCUGCUUGCUGUUACCUACUUUUUACAGGCAUCAUAAUAAAAGCUAGACUAUUUCUUUGGGGGGAAAGAGACUUAUUUAAUGUAAUUUAAAAAACUUUUCCAAUAGAAAAUGAAAUAUUAUUGAAAAUAAUAUCUAUUUUUUAGCUUUCAGCAAUUGAUGGUGCUUUGUUGUGGUGUCUGCUGGAAGUCUACUGCCAUUAUAGGGAACCUUGCUUGUUAGCUUCUCUAGAUCUCUAUUCUAAACAAUCUGUUAGUGAUGAUAAAUUCUGUAGGAGGGUCUAUUCUGAGCCGUUAACUUCCUGUAAGGGGAAAAUGGGUGGGUUACCAGAAAUACCAUUGAAGCAGGGUGGGCUGUGGGGUGGAAGGUUGGGGUAUUUGUCUUGAGAAUUAAAAACUACGAAACACUUUUGUACACAACUGAUUUUUUAAAAAAUAAACACAUUUUUAAAGAUGUUGAAUUUUUCCCCCCUUAUUGGGAAUUCUUAAAAAUAAAUGCAUGCAUGUUUUCCCCUGAAAA